AGUCUCGGAGGCGGCGCCGCAGGGGAUUGAGGGGUUGACUGAGCGUUGCGAGCCUUAGCUUUCUCCCGAACGCCAGCGCUGAGGACACGAUGUCGCGGCUCUCCCGCUCACUGCUUUGGGCCGCCACCUGCCUGGGCGUGCUCUGCGUGCUGUCCGCGGACAAGAACACGACCCAGCACCCGAACGUGACGACUUUAGCGCCCAUCUCCAACGUAACCUCGGCGCCGGUGACGUCCCUCCCGCUGGUCACCACUCCGGCACCAGAAACCUGUGAAGGUCGAAACAGCUGCGUUUCCUGUUUUAAUGUUAGCGUUGUUAAUACUACCUGCUUUUGGAUAGAAUGUAAAGAUGAGAGCUAUUGUUCACAUAACUCAACAGUUAGUGAUUGUCAAGUGGGGAACACGACAGACUUCUGUUCCGUUUCCACGGCCACUCCAGUGCCAACAGCCAAUUCUACAGCUAAACCCACAGUUCAGCCCUCCCCUUCUACAACUUCCAAGACAGUUACUACAUCAGGUACAACAAAUAACACUGUGACUCCAACCUCACAACCUGUGCGAAAGUCUACCUUUGAUGCAGCCAGUUUCAUUGGAGGAAUUGUCCUGGUCUUGGGUGUGCAGGCUGUAAUUUUCUUUCUUUAUAAAUUCUGCAAAUCUAAAGAACGAAAUUACCACACUCUGUAAACAGACCCAUUGAAUUAAUAAGGACUGGUGAUUCAUUUGUGUAACUCACUGAAGCCAAAAUACUAUCUUUUAAGAUGUCCCACAUGGAAGACGCUAUUCCAGGAUCUUUAAAUUUCCAUGGAUGCAUAUAGGAUGUUUGGGAGCAUCAUCCGUGAAGAAAAAAUCAAUUAAAUCAUUGUGUUCAACAGGAAUAUUUAAAAUAUUCUGCAUGAAUCCUGUGGCUGUCUUAUUUUAAAUAGCUGCUGCUGUGGGAUUAUAUUUUUUUUCCUUAACAUGCCAAAUAUAACUUUCUGAAAGUGAUGGAAAAUGUUGUCUUGUGCAGACAACAUCAUGGCUCUUGGCAGUUUAAAUUUAGUAAUUUUAAUUUAGUGAACAGAAUUGAGAAGAACGUGCCAAAUGAGAAUCAAUUAGGUGGAUUUUUGGCUGUCAUUUCAAAAGUGGAAUAAAUUUAUUAAUUUAGUAGUACUAAAUGGUAUCCUUAGAUUAAAAUUUUGUGCUUGAUAACAGCUGUUUUUUCUACAUUAGAAAUAAGAUGCCACACAAGGAACUACAUUCCAGAUUUAAAGAAAUGAAAGGAUACCAUUAGUGUGUAUAACAGAUUAUUGUUCAUACUUGUAAAGCAUCUUAUGUCAUUGAGAAUAUAAAGAACAGUGCCUUAGAAGACAGUGAAAGGUAAGCUCUAGCUUAAUGUCUAUGAUUUGUUCUUUGACAUUAAGGAAGGUAAGGAUUGGUCAGAGGAUGUAACUUGAUGUGAGCAGUAGUAAACCUGUUUUAGAUAUCAUACUGUUAAUAUUUUAUUGAAAAUUUAUUUCAGAGCGGAGAAACUUAAGCUAAAGUCUGUUAUACAGAAUUGAAAGCCUUCGUAUCUUGAACCUCCCAACAUUUUUCUUAUGGCUGUUGAAAAGUAUAGAGCUAAAUUGAUUUAAUUACACUUUCCUUUGUACUUUAAAAAAAAGUAUGCUAGCACUAUUGUACCUUGAAAGGAUUUCCACCAGACUGUCUUGAGUAGUGACUUCUUUGGUGAGGCAAGAAGGAUAUACAUUAUUUUAGAAUCAUUUACUAUUUAAAUGAGACAAUCAUAUUAUUUUAGAAUCAUUUAUUUUAAAUGAGACAAUCAUUUUAAGUUUUAAGAUAACAGAAGUGACCAAUGUAAUUUCACAACACCUAAGGAUUUUUUGGUUGAUCAGGUUACUGUAGAUUUUUACUGAUUGUCCUGGAUGAAUAGACUGUGCUUUUUCUUUUUCUCUCCCUUCCUUCUUGGUUUCCCAUAGUAUAAUAAGCAUGCAUACUUUAACUUCUAUAGUUUUCUCCUUUAGAGGGUCGUCUUCAGUUUUAGAGGUUUACUUCUCCCUUGCCUUUGACUCAUUGGACUAGUGCAGAGGCUUUAAGUAGUUUAAAAUGGGCUUUUGCUUUUCUAGGUCAUUAACGUUUUUUAUUUAGUUUCUUUAGCCAAUAGUGGCUGAGUUUCGCACUUGAUUUUCAAUAUUUUAUAGUAAGAAAUGACAAACUGCUUUGUUUCAUUUCAUAAACAAACUCUGCAUUUAGAUAACUAUUAAAGGUUGUUAAGAUGAAGAUUUACUGUUUCUUUGUUACUCGUUGGUACAGCUGUUUGUUUUACUUGCACAUUUGUACAUAUACUUAAUGUUUUCAAGUGCCUUAAUUGUUUAAAAUCUCUGGCUUCAAAGUUUCUUGGGGAAAGGUCGGUUUACCUCACAUUUUUUGUUUCCAUUAGUAAUAUUCUAGGUACCUCACAAAAUGUAUUAUGGUGCCAUGGCUGUUAGUUUUUAGUGAGUGCUGUAGGAUUAAUUCGAAAAUAGGCAGAAUUCCAUUCCUCCCAAGGUGGCAAAAAUUAGCUAUACUGAUGUAAUUGUCAUUUACCUGGGUAUGAAUUCCCUGACACACAUUCAUGUCAACAUAUGUAGCAAAUUUUGUGAAAACAUAACAAUUUGAAGCUUCUGUAAUUUUGAGCACUGCUCUAACAACAAGCAUAAUAUAAAAUUAGUUAGAUUUUGCAAGUCUACAAAUGAGCUCUUGCAACAGAACUCACAGCCUUUUUACUUUUUUCCCCUAACUUUAGCAAUGUAGUAUCUUGAGCCAUUAAUUUUUGGGUUUUUUUAAAAUCCAGAAGGUAUAUAGAAACCUUUUCAGAUUUUUCAUCUGAUUUGUUCUUGCAGAUGUUCUUCUAUCAAAUACCUUAUUUUACCUUACAGAUAUUUGUUGCACAGGCAGAUACUGCUGUAUUUAGACAUUUCUAUUUCAGUUCAUUAAAAACUGCAAAACCAAUCUGUAUCAUGUACCAAACUGACUUAAAAUAAAUCUACAUGUUUAUUGAAUUAA